CCUCUCCCUCUAGCAUAGAAAAUGCAAUCCUGAAACACUGCACAGCAGGGCUUCUCAAUUCGGGAUCACAUUUGAAUCACCUGAGGAGAUUUUAAAUCAUACUGAUGCCGAGGCCUCACCCAGACCAAUUCAAUCAGAAUCCCUAAUAGCAGAGCUAAACAAGGGUAAGGUCUAAAAGCAUUUCCAGGUGAUUCUAAUGGGCAGCCAAUACUGAGAACCACUGUUCUUAUGUAAGAAGCACAUCUUACCUAUAUUUCCUAGGAAGACCAGUUGAUGAGGUCAUAUGCAAAAGUUCCCAUUUAUUGGUUUAGUAUAAUUGUGCAAAUUAGAAUUAACCCCUAAGUGUAUAAAGAGUAGAGCUGGUUAAAAACAUAGCCUGUGCUAAGUUUAAUUGUACAGUAAUUUACAUUUGUGUGGUACUUCCAAGUUUCCCAAAUGCCCUCAUAUUUGUUAUCCACCUGUACAUUUAAACCAAUUCCCAGAGGUUAGAAAAGGAUUCUUAUCUUAUCUGAGAGACAGUAUAGCACCAUGGUUAAAAGCUCAGACUCUGACACCAGACAGUCUGGGUGCAAAUCCUGGCUCUGCUGUUGCCCUCAGACAGGAUUUCUUAGCUUCUCUGUGUAUCAGUUUUCUCAUCUGUGAAAGGAGGAUGAAUAUAAGACCUUAUGCGAUGCUAAUGUAGGAUUAAAUUCCCUACUACAAGAAAAUGGUCUUAGAACAAUGCCUGGAACAUGUGGCUGAGCACGGUGCCAGGUUCCAGAUUCCAUUGCUUGGAGCCAUGGCCGCGACGCUGGUGGUCAUCUGCACAGCAGUCAUCGUGGUGGUCGCGUUGACUAGAAAGAAGAAAGCCCUCAGAAUCCAUUCUGUGGAAGGUGACCUCAGGAGAAAAUCAGCUGGACAGGAGGAAUGGAGCCCCAGUGCUCCCUCACCCCCAGGAAGCUGUGUCCAGGCAGAAGCUGCACCUGCUGGGCUCUGUGGAGAGCAGCGGGGAGAGGACUGUGCCGAGCUGCAUGACUACUUCAAUGUCCUGAGUUACAGAAGCCUGGGUAACUGCAGCUUCUUCACAGAGACUGGUUAGCAACCAGAGGCAUCUUCUGGAAGAUACACUUUUGUCUUUGCUAUUAUAGAUGAAUAUAUAAGCAGCUGUACUCUCCAUCAGUGCUGCGUGUGUGUGUGUGUGUGUAUGUGUGUGUGUGUUCAGUUGAGUGAAUAAAUGUCAUCCUCUUCUCCAUCUUCAUUUCCUUGGCCUUUUCGUUCUAUUCCAUUUUGCAUUAUGGCAGGCCUAGGGUGAGUAACGUGGAUCUUGAUCAUAAAUGCAAAAUUAAAAAAUAUCUUGACCUGGUUUUAAAUCUGGCAGUUUGAGCAGAUCCUAUGUCUCUGAGAGACACAUUCCUCAUAAUGGCCAGCAUUUUGGGCUACAAGGUUUUGUGGUUGAUGAUGAGGAUGGCAUGACUGCAGAGCCAUCCUCAUCUCAUUUUUUCACGUCAUUUUCAGUAACUUUCACUCAUUCAAAGGCAGGUUAUAAGUAAGUCCUGGUAGCAGCCUCUAUGGGGAGAUUUGAGAGUGACUAAAUCUUGGUAUCUGCCCUCAAGAACUUACAGUUAAAUGGGGAGACAAUGUUGUCAUGAAAAGGUAUUAUAGUAAGGAGAGAAGGAGACAUACACAGGCCUUCAGGAAGAGACGACAGUUUGGGGUGAGGUAGUUGGCAUAGGCUUAUCUGUGAUGAAGUGGCCUGGGAGCACCAAGGGGAUGUUGAGGCUAGUCUGGGAGGAGCAGGAGUUUUGUCUAGGGAACUUGUAGGAAAUUCUUGGAGCUGAAAGUCCCACAAAGAAGGCCCUGGCACCAAGGGAGUCAGCAAACUUCAGAUUUUAUUCUCUGGGCAGGCAUUUCAAGUUUCCUUUUGCUGUGACAUACUCAUCCAUUAGACAGCCUGAUACAGGCCUGUAGCCUCUUCCGGCCGUGUGUGCUGGGGAAGCCCCAGGAAACGCACAUGCCCACACAGGGAGCCAAGUCGUAGCAUUUGGGCCUUGAUCUACCUUUUCUGCAUCAAUACACUCUUGAGCCUUUGAAAAAAGAACGUUUCCCACUAAAAAGAAAAUGUGGAUUUUUAAAAUAGGGACUCUUCCUAGGGGAAAAAGGGGGGCUGGGAGUGAUAGAGGGUUUAAAAAAUAAACACCUUCAAACUAACUUCUUCGAACCCUUUUAUUCACUCCCUGACGACUUUGUGCUGGGGUUGGGGUAACUGAACCGCUUAUUUCUGUUUAAUUGCAUUCAGGCUGGAUCUUAGAAGACUUUUAUCCUUCCACCAUCUCUCUCAGAGGAAUGAGCGGGGAGGUUGGAUUUACUGGUGACUGAUUUUCUUUCAUGGGCCAAGGAACUGAAAGAGAAUGUGAAGCAAGGUUGUGUCUUGCGCAUGGUUAAAAAUAAAGCAUUGUCCUGCUUCCUAAGACUUAGACUGGGGUUGACAAUUGUUUUAGCAACAAGACAAUUCAACUAUUUCUCCUAGGAUUUUUAUUAUUAUUAUUUUUUCACUUUUCUACCAAAUGGGUUACAUAGGAAGAAUGAACUGAAAUCUGUCCAGAGCUCCAAGUCCUUUGGAAGAAAGAUUAGAUGAACGUAAAAAUGUUGUUGUUUGCUGUGGCAGUUUACAGCAUUUUUCUUGCAAAAUUAGUGCAAAUCUGUUGGAAAUAGAACACAAUUCACAAAUUGGAAGUGAACUAAAAUGUAAUGACGAAAAGGGAGUAGUGUUUUGAUUUGGAGGAGGUGUAUAUUCGGCAGAGGUUGGACUGAGAGUUGGGUGUUAUUUAACAUAAUUAUGGUAAUUGGGAAACAUUUAUAAACACUAUUGGGAUGGUGAUAAAAUACAAAAGGGCCUAUAGAUGUUAGAAAUGGGUCAGGUUACUGAAAUGGGAUUCAAUUUGAAAAAAAUUUUUUUAAAUAGAACUCACUGAACUAGAUUCUCCUCUGAGAACCAGAGAAGACCAUUUCAUAGUUGGAUUCCUGGAGACAUGCGCUAUCCACCACGUAGCCACUUUCCACAUGUGGCCAUCAACCACUUAAGAUGGGGUUAGUUUAAAUCAAGAUGUGCUGUUAUAAUUGGUAUAAGCAUAAAAUCACACUAGAUUCUGGAGAUUUAAUAUGAAUAAUAAGAAUACUAUUUCAGUAGUUUUGGUAUAUUGUGUGUCAAAAAUGAUAAUAUUUUGGAUGUAUUGGGUGAAAUAAAAUAUUAACAUUA